GGUUUCGCCAUGUUGGCCAGGCUGGUCAUGGACUUCUGACCUCAAGUGAUCCGCCUGCCUUGGCCUCCCAAGUGCUGGGAUUCCAGGCGUGAGCCACCACGCCCUGCCACUAUCAAUCUUAGAACAUUUUCAUCACCCCCCAAAAGAAACUCCGUACCUAUUCCCAGUCAUUCCUCGUCUCCCCUCUAGCACUCUGGCUCUAGACAACCACCCGUCUGCUUCCUAUCUCUAUGGAUUUGCCAAUAUUAGACAUUUUGUAAAACUGAUCAUAUAACAUGUGACCUUUUGUGUCUGGCUUCUUUCCAUAAUGUUUUCAGGGUCCACCUAUGUUGUAGCAUAUGUCAGGCUUUCAUUCCUUUUCAUGGCCGAAUAAUGUUCCAUUGUAUGGAUGUGCCAUGUUUAUUUACCCAUUCAUCAGCUGAUGGACACUUGGCUCCUUUUGGGUACUGGGAAUAAUGCUGCGAGGAACAUUCACCUGCACGCGUUUUCAUGUGGACAUUGUGUUCAUACCUCUUGAGCCGAUCCAAGGACUGGAGUUGCUGGGUCCUAUGGUAACUCUGUGUUAAUGUUUUUGCGAAACUGCCAGAGUGUUUUCCAAAAUGUCCGCAGCAUUUUCCAUUCCCACCAGCAGUGUAGGAGGGUUCCAGUUUCUUCCUAUCCUUGUCAGCACUUGUUAUUGGCUAUUUCUUUGACUGCAGCCACCCACAAAAUAACUUUAAUAGACUGAUUUUAUUUAUCCUCACAUUCACUUCGUGAGCCUUUGUUUUGGUUCCACCACUGAGGGAAACUGAGGCUCAGGGUGAUCGAGUCAGUGGUUGAAGACCCCAUGGAGAGAUACCUGGAUCAGAUACCUAAGGAACGCUGGGGCAGGGGGCCCCGUCUGCCUCGGCAUCCCCAGGAUUCUCGAGGCCUCUGGCUCCCUUGGAGAAAGGAGCUGGAGCUGGUGGAGGAUGUGUGGCGAGGGGAGGCGCAGGACCUCCUCUCCCAGAUCGCCCAGCUGCAGGAGGAGAACAAGCAGCUCAUGACCAACCUCUCCCACAAGGAUGUCAAUUUCUCAGAGGAGGAGUUCCAGAAGCAUGAAGGUCUCUGUCUUCAACGCUGGAGUGCAGUGGCGCAAUUAUAGUUCACCAUAGCCUCAACCUCCCAGGCUCAAAAGAUUCUCCCACCUCAGUCUUCUAAGUAGCUGGGAUGACAGGCAUGUCAGAGCGGGAGCGACAGGUGAUGAAGAAGCUGAAGGAGGUGGUGGACAAACAACGCGACGAGAUCCGCGCCAAGGACAGGGAGCUGGGCCUGAAAAAUGAGGACGUUGAGGCUUUACAGCAGCAGCAGACACGGCUGAUGAAGAUCAACCAUGACCUUCGGCACCGGGUCACGGUGGUGGAGGCCCAGGGGAAAGCCCUGAUCGAACAGAAGGUGGAGCUGGAGGCAGACCUGCAGACCAAGGAGCAGGAGAUGGGCAGCCUGCGAGCAGAGCUGGGGAAGUUGCGAGAGAGGCUGCAGGGGGAGCACAGCCAGAAUGGGGAGGAGGAGCCUGAGACGGAGCCGGUGGGAGAGGAGAGCAUCUCCGACGCAGAGAAGGUGGCCAUGGAUCUCAAGGACCCCAACCGCCCCCGGUUCACCCUGCAGGAGCUGCGGGACGUGCUGCACGAGAGGAACGAGCUCAAGUCCAAGGUGUUCUUGCUGCAGGAGGAGCUGGCUUACUAUAAGAGUGAAGAAAUGGAAGAGGAAAACCGAAUACCCCAACCCCCACCCAUCGCCCACCCGAGGACGUCCCCCCAGCCGGAGUCGGGCAUCAAGCGACUGUUUAGCUUCUUCUCCCGAGAUAAGAAGCGCCUGGCCAACACACAGAGAAACGUGCACAUCCAGGAGUCCUUUGGACAGUGGGCAAACACCCACCGCGAUGACGGUUACACAGAGCAAGGACAGGAAGCCCUGCAGCAUCUGUGACCUUGGCCCAUCUCCACCCUCCAACCUGGACUGCCCGCCACCAGCGCCUGCAACCGAACUGCAGCCCAGGGGUCAUUGCUGCCUCAAGCCUCUCGGUGCAGAUGCACCCUGAAAACUGACCCCUCAAACAGACUGUCUGAUUUGAGGAUGGACAUUGAAAAACUGACGCCAAACUCUAAAGAAAUGUUUAUUUAUACCCAGGGCUAUCACUGUUUCUAAUAGAUGACUCUGAUCCCGUAGGAUAUAUAUUUAAUAAUCCCACAAACGGAGGCCAGACUUCUGCGUUAACUUCAGUAACACAAGCUUCUUUAAGCCAAAUACAUCACUUGCCACUAUCAUUGCUGUUUGACUUGCUUUGUAUAAAAUGCUAUGUGUAGAGGUUUUAUUAUCACAGGUGACAUAGUUCAGCAGGAGGCAUGGAAGGGCUAGAUCUUCAUUAGUUACAUUCAUGAAAUUGUGAUGGUAACGUAUUAUACAGAAUGUAUCCAUCAGGCAGACAAGGGGUCUGAAGUCACAGGCUCAGUAGCCCAACUCAGACACAAAGCCACAGACAAUAUGGAUGAUGGUCCUCUUACCCAGAAACUGGAGACAACUUUGCAGGCACCCUGGCUGCGUUCCUGAUAAUGCCUAGAGCAUGUAGCAAUGUUCAAGGCAGGUGCCUUGGAAUCUGCUGUGAGUUAUGCAGUACUAACCAAACAAAGUUGCUAAGGAUGAGAUGUUGCAACAUUUCUUGUGUGCACUUUUUUUUCCUGACAUCUUUUUUUCCUUUUAGGAUUCAUUAAGUCAUAUACUUAGUCCCCUGCAAAGAAGAAGACAGAUGUCCCAGAGCAGACUGAAAGCGGGGCGUGGGAUCCUAGGCAAUGCAGGAGGGCAGGUGGGGGAGCUGUAGCAGAACAAGGGUGCUAGGUGGGAAGCUGGCUUGGGGACCACACGUCUGGCUGACUCACAGGGCUAUAGCAGCAGACAGAGAGCCAGAUGCUCUACUGCAACUGGUGAGUUGGAGGCUUGCCCACAUAACACUGUCUUUCUCUCCACCCGCCAAGCAUCCAGGGCACAGGGCUGGUUGCUCACAGAUUGAGCGAGGUAGCACCUCCUACCAGCACUCAAGUUUAUCAGGGCCGCGUUCUAAACAUUCUACUGAAGUUUGCUAAGAAACCAUUAGGUGAGGCUGGGCACAGUGGCUCACGCCUGCUAUCCCAGCACUUUGGGAGGCCGAGGCAGGUGGGUCACUUGAGGUCCGGAGUUCGAGACCAGCUUGGCCAACACGGUGAAACCCCAUCUCUACAAAAAUACAAAAAAAUUAGCCAGGCGAGGUGGUGCAUGCCUAUAAUCCCAGCUGCUCAGGAGGCCGAGACAGGAGAAUUCCUUGAACCUAGGAGGCAGAGGUUGCAGUGAGCCUAGAUCGUGCCAUUGCACUCCAGCCUGGGCGACAGAGUGAGACUUCAUCUAAAAAAAAAAAAAAAAAGAAAGAAAGAAACCAUCAGGUGAAUUUGCAGAAUCUAGAAUGGACUCUGCUUCCAGAUUGCCGAAAAAAAGAAAUGAUCAGACAGGGUAAUUAUUGCUGCGUUAGAGCAGUGUUUCUCAAACCUGAGUGCCCAUUAGAAUUAUUAGAAUUUAUUCUCAAAGAGUAUAGAAGCAGGUAUACUGAUGAAUUUCUCUCCCACCCCUGGCCACCUUUGUUGCCCUUCCAACAGGUAACCAAAAUUGCCAGUUUCUUGGUUAUCUUUCCUAAACACUAAAUGUCUCUCUUUUUUUUGAGAUAGUCUUGCUCUAUUGCCCAAGCCAAAGUAUAGUGGCACCAUCUCUGCUCACUGCAACUUCCGCCUCUUGAGUUCAAGCAAUUCUCAUGCCUGAGCCUCCCAAGUAGCUGGGACUACAUGUGUGUGCCACCAUACCUGACUAAUUUUUGUAUUUUUAGUAAAGACGGGGUUUCACCAUGUUGGCCAGGCUGGUCUCGAGGUCUCGAACUCCUGACCUCAAGUGAUUCACCUGCCUUGGCCUCUCAAAGUGCUGGGAUUACAGGUGUGAGCCACUGUGGCUGGCCUUUUUUUUUUUUUUUUUUUUGGACACAGGGUCUCACUCUGUCACCUAGGCUGGAGUACAGUGGCACUAUCAUAGCUCAUUGCAGCUAUGAACCCCUGGGCUCAAGCAAUCCUCCCACCUCAGCCUCCCAAGUAGCUGGUACUACUGAUGUGCACCACCAUGCCCAGCUAAUUAUUUUUUGUAGAGACCAGGUCUUACUUUGUUGCCUAAGCUGGUCUCAAACUCCUGGGCUCAAGUGAUCCUCACACCCCAGCCUCCCAAAGUGCUGGGAAUUCAGGUGUGAGCCACCGUGCCUGGCCAAAUGUCACUUUUUUGAUAAGUCAGCAGAUCCAGCUCUUGAGCACAUCAGAGGCUAGAUAAUCGGGACAGAAAGGAAAAAUCAAUCCAUCAGAAAGUUUAUACAUGCAAUUAUGUAAAAUAAAAUCAAGAACAAAAAGCAUA